CAUUUUGAUGUCUAGAAUCAGGGGAUCCAGGAUCAUCACCAAGGUCAUUUUCCCAGGUAUGGAGGGGUCUUUCUGCUUCUUUCUUGUCAUGCACAGCUGCUGAGGAAGGGGCUGGGAGUAAAGACAGUGAAAUGGGGAGGAGGAGUCCAUUCAAACCGAGAAACAAAGUGUUUGGUUUUUCUUACCCCUGGUGUAGAAGCUACCAACCUUUUCCAAGAAAGAGGGCCUGGCCCCCUUCUCGGGUCUGGCUGGGUGCCUGCUGUGCCUCUCUGGCCUCCCCUCCGAAGGGCACCAUUCCCUCGGGUGAGUACUACCGGCCUGCACCGUCUUCCAGUGGGGACAGCCUGAGAAGAGAGUCUGGAGCCUUACUUCAGUACCUUCCUUCACUGGCCUCACCCUGUGCAAAUCAUGCCACACGCUGCAGCCUCCUUUUCCCUAUCUAUAAAAUAAAAAUGACCCUGCUCUAUCUCACUGGGCUGGCAAGAACACACUGUUGUUACCUUGCAGACAGAUGUGCUGAGGCUGUAGAAAGUGCUUUUUAUUUGGUUGGGAGCUUGUGCAUAAAUGCGAGAGGGGCUGCACAUCUGACGGACUAGAGGUGACUCAUGGCUGAACCGGAACAGGACAUCGGGGAGAAGCCAGCAGCCAUGCUGAACUCUCCACAGGGCCCUGUGAAAAGCUCUUCACCUCCUCUGCCCUCUGGAUCUAGUGAAGCCUAUUCAUCCUUCAGAUGUCAGCUCAAAUAAUCAACCUUCAUGGAGGCCUCCCUUGACCCCUAACAUGCUUUCAAAGUACUGUGUAUUUCACAUUCAUCAUGCCCCGACAACUGUGAUUUCCCAUUUAUUAAUAUCUGUCUCUUCUGCUGGCCUGCAAACUCCAGGAGCACAGAGACAUCUUUGGGAUUUUUGAACAUGAUUUCCCCAGGGCUUAGCCCAGUGCCUGGUGCAAAGCAGGCUUUCAACAUGUUCAGUGGAUAUUGUAAGAAAGAAAGAAAUACACAAAAGGCCUGGCAUAUGCAAAGCACUCUAAAUAUUCACUCCUUUCCCUUCCCUCUGGGUGAGAAAAUUUCUCCUUAUAAAGACACCCUCCUAACUGUAUCUCUGCUAGAGAACUGAAGACAUAAAGCACUCUGUGCCAAAAAUAUUUAAGUAAAAACUUGAGCUAAGCACAGAGAUUAUAAAUAUUUCUUCCCCAGAUUACGCACCAUUUAAAAAUACUGUCUCAGCUCCUUUUCAUGAUUUGGGUGGUGAUUAAAGAAAAUUACUCUUCAA